AGAGAGUGGGGACGUCCGGCUUCGGAGCGGGAGUGUUCGUUGUGCCAGCGACUAAAAAGAGAAUUAAAUAUGGGUGAUGUUGAGAAAGGCAAGAAGAUUUUUAUUAUGAAGUGUUCCCAGUGCCACACCGUUGAAAAGGGAGGCAAGCACAAGACUGGGCCAAAUCUCCAUGGUCUCUUUGGGCGGAAGACAGGUCAGGCCCCUGGAUACUCUUACACAGCCGCCAAUAAGAACAAAGGCAUCAUCUGGGGAGAGGAUACACUGAUGGAGUAUUUGGAGAAUCCCAAGAAGUACAUCCCUGGAACAAAAAUGAUCUUUGUCGGCAUUAAGAAGAAGGAAGAAAGGGCAGACUUAAUAGCUUAUCUCAAAAAAGCUACUAAUGAGUAAUAAUUGGCCACUGCCUUAUUUAUUACAAAACAGAAAUGUCUCAUGACUUUUUUAUGUGUACCAUCCUUUAAUAGAUCUCAUACACCAGAAUUCAGAUCAUGAAUGACUGACAGAAUAUUUUGUUGGGCAGUCCUGAUUUAAAACUAAGACUGGCUUGUGGUUAAAUGAAUAUGUUCAGUUUUUGAAUUUUAAUAGUAACUCCAAUUCAGUAAAUGGUAUCACUGUUUACCCCUUUUAAAGAUAUGAUUAGACUUCGUUAGUAAUGUUCAACUUUUCACAAAGAUGGUGAGUGCCAUCUUAAAACUUACUGGAGAUUGGUUUUAUAUUUAGAUUUAUAUAACUGGUUAUGUGAAUAUAUUUAAAUACUGGGGAAAUUGCUUCACUGUCUUAGAACCAAGCAAGAUUCACCUGUGUUUUGUGUUCAUGUUCAUUUGCCUCUUAAAGGCAAGGGUUGAAGAUAAAUAAGGUAGCAAUGUCUAUAGUUUUGGCCUUAACUAUGCCAAUCUAAUUAUAAUUCCCUGUAUUUAAAAUGGUUUCUUUUACUUAUUGAAAGGCAUUUUAGUGUGGUUUAUGUGUAAUAUUAAAGAUUAUUCAACACCUCUCACAUCUUACAGAUCUAUAAGGUCACAUGCUUUUAAAAUAGUAGCAAGUUAAACUUCACUCUUGAAUUCUUUACAAUCUAAGUCAAACUAAGUUAUAAUUUAGGAUUGUCUUUAAACAGCCAUUCAGAAACAAAACUGUAGAACUGUGUAUUUGAUUGGGAAUGGUGCUUUUGCCAACUUAAAAGGAUUAAAGUAACGGAGAUAUACACAAAUUUUAAAAUUAUGUGUGAUCACAAGACUAAAGAUAAUUAAAAAGAAAACCACAGAUCAUGACUUUUUGACUGUGCUUGAUUUCAUGACUGAUGCACAAAUUUUAAUGAUUAAAAAGUGCAGGAGCCCUAAAUGUCAGUGCAGCAGCCCUAAAUGUCAGUGCAGCAGUGUUAACCAGUCAUGGUGCUAGAUUGUUUACUUGGUUUUCUAGGACUGCCUCAACUAGAAUAACACUUCACUAAUUGACUCUUAGUUUCUUUGCUCAGAUUGAGAACUGCAGCAUUUAUGCCAGACAUGGACAGAGGAAUGCCUGUGGUCAUAGUUUUGUGAUGUGUAACAGUGUAUAAUUACAUACUGAAUUAUUUCAUGCAUAGUCUGUGCCAUACACAUUUAGAGUAGUCCUUGGAGAUUUUAUGGAGAUGGUGAGCACAAGGUAAGUCAUAAAGAAUAAUGAGAAAAUAAAUCUAUGCUGGUGCAGCUGAGAACUGUAUCUUUGUGGGACAGUGAGAAGACUGAGAAGAUGUGAAUCCAUGGUCUCAAAGGUGAUAGGGACGAUUAGAUAGGUGUUUUAAGGCCUGAAAGCAAUUUAUAACAUAUGAGUCUUAUUUUUAUUUAUAGAAAUGUGGAAAGCUUGCUGUAAUUCAUAUUUGAAGUCCUAGUCUGAGUUCUGGUGGGGAAUUUAAAAAUGCAUCCUGGAAAUCCUUUAAAGAUUUCAGACUUUGAAAGGCCUUGUAGCAGAGGACUUGGUGACUGUAUAAAGUUAGUGGUAUUCAGGGACAGUGUAGCAAGUAGCUUACAAGGGGACAAUUCUGGACUAAUGAGAAAGACCUGAAGUGAAGGCUAGAGAGUUGAUUUUUUUUUUUUUUGGCAUCCUGGAAAUGAUACAGGAAACAUAUUAAGAUAGAUACAGAAAUGUGUUCAACCUUCCAUCUUGGCUAGUUGUGGCGUUUAGUUUGUUUUUUGAGACAUGGUCACGCUGUGUCGCCAAGGCUGGAGUGCAGUGGUGCGAUCUCGGCUGGCUGCAACCUCUAUUUCCCAGGCUCAAGCGAUUCUCUCACUUCAGCUUCCCAAGUAGCUGGGACUACAGGUGUUCGCCACCAUGCCCAGCUAAUUUUUUUGUAGAGAUGGAGUUUUGCCAUGUGGUCCCAGGCUGGUCUCAAACUCCUGAGCUCAAGCAAUCCGUCCACUUGCCUUGGCUCCCCAAAGUGCUGGGAUUACAGGCGUGAGCCACCAGGCCCUGCCUGGUUUUCAAAUUCAGAAAUCUUAUUAUUUAACCCAGAAGUAAUCAGCCCAGUAGUAACUUAGGUUUAAUUUUUUUUCAGGUUUAAAAUUUUUCUCAUUUAUUUUUUCUGAGACGGAGUUUCGCCCUUUUCGCCCAGGCUGAGUACAGUGGUGCAAUCUCACUGCAACCUCCGCCUUCCAGUUGCAAGUGAUUCUCCUGCCUCAGCCUCCUGAGUAGCUGGGAUUACAGGCACCCGCCACCACGCCUGGCUAAUUUUUGUAUUUUUAGUGGAGAUGGUGUUUCACCAUGUUGGCCAGACUGGUCUUGGACUCCUGACCUCGUGAUCCACCCACCUUGGCCUCCCAAAGUUCUAGGAUUACAGGUGUGAGCCACCACGUCCGGCCAAUUUUUCUCAUUUCUAUGCCUCCUAUAUUAAGGUCUGUGUUGGCACAGAUGAGUAACUGCCAUGUUCUAGGUCAGUUAUACCCAAGCACUUCUGGUGGUUUAAAAUGUGAUUCUGUAACUUUUUUAUUUUUAUUUUUUUGAGAUAAUUUCACUCUUGUUGCCCAGGCUGGAGUGCAAUGGCGUGAUCGCUGCUCACCGCAACCUCCGCCUUCCAGGUUCAAGCGAUUCUCCUGACUCAGCCUCUCAAGUAGCUGGGAUUACAAGCAUGCGCCACCAUGCCCAGCUUAUUUUGUGUUUUUAGUAGAGACAGGGUUUCUCCAUGCUGGACAGGCUGGUCUUGAACUCCCGACGUCAGGUGAUCUACCUGCCUCGGCCUCCCAAAGUGCUGGGAUUACAGGCGUGAGCCACCACGCCUGGCCAAUUAUGUAAUUUUUUAAAAAGGACAUUUCUAUCAGGGAUAUAUACCUUCAGAAAUAAGGAAAUAGGGGAAAAAAAGAGCACUAUAAACCACAUGUUUUCAUUUCUAGUGCUUCGCUGUAAGUGGCUAGGUUGGUAGAAUCAAAAACAAGGGCCAGAUGUAUUUAAGGGGUAUUCAGAUGCCACCUACAUGCUUAUUUUGUCUAGAACAGUGCUGUCUAAUAGAACUUUCUGUGACGAUGGAUAUUUUGUAGACUUUUGCUGUCCAGUGUGGUAGCCACUAACCACAUGUGGCUGUUAAGCCCUUGAAAUAUAGCUAGUGUGACUAGAAAGUAUUUUAUUUUAAAUUUACAUAGGCACAAGUGGCUAGUGGCUACUGUAUUGACAUUCUGGGUCUAGGACUAGAACCAGUGGUCUGUAACAAAAGUACUUUCUCUUUACUCUAUUAAAUCUAGAAUUAGCCGGGCAUGGUCGCUCAUGCCUGUAAUCCCAGCACUUUGGGAGGCCAAGGCAGGCAGAUCACUUGAGGUCAGGCGUUUGAGACCAGCCUGGUCAACAUGGCGAAACCCUGUCUCUACAAAAAACAUAAAAAUUAGCCAGGUGUGGUGGUGGGCACCUGUAAUCUCAGCUACUUGGGAGGCUGAGGCACAAGAAUCACUUGAACUUGGGAGGUGGAGGUUGCAGUGAGCCAAGAUUGUGCCACUGCACUCAAGCCUGGGUGACGAGUGAAACUGUCUCCAAAAAAAAAAAAAAAUCUAGAAUUCUUGGAAGUACAUUAUAUUGCCCUUCAGAAUAGAUUCCAGUUCCUGUUGUGCUCACCUUUAUAAUUUUACCAUAAGUUUUACCUAUUCGUAAGUUGGCAGUUUUAGAUAGAUAACAUUCUGGUGGUAGCUAGGGAUUUACCUUUUGUCAUCCUUUUCCUGCACUUCUCUUGAAUUCCUUUAUAGAUGUACAGUUUUGCUUUAACCACUGAAGAUUGCUGUAAAUUAUAAAGGGUGUGAUAGAAUCCACAUGGCUGUCAAGAAGGAGAUCUUACCAAGGACAGUUGACUGACUAGUCUCAGAUUGUUUCAUAUCAUUUAUACUUGGGUAAGAGUAAACUAGAUAACUGGGCGUCGUGGUGCACACCUGUAGUCCCAGCCACUCUGAGGCAGGAGGACUGCUUGUGCCCAGAAGUUCGAGGCUGCAGUGUAGCUGUGAUUGUGCUACUGCACUCCAGCCUGGGCAACAGAUAAAGGAAACUCCAUCUCUUUUAAAAAAAAAAAAAGUGGUCUGGGUGCAGUAGGUCAUGCCUGCAAUCCCAGCACUUUGGGAGGCCAAGGCAGGCAGAUCACCUGAGGUCAGGAGCUUGAGACCAGCCUGGCCAACAUGGUGAAACCCCAUCUCUACCAAAAAUAUAAAAACUAGCUGGGCGUGGUGGCGGCACCUGUAAUUGCAGCUAUUUGAGAGGCUGAGGCAGGAGAAUCGCUUGAACCUGGGAGAUGGGGGUUGCAGUGAGCCAAGACCGCCCCAUCGCACUCCAGCCUGGGCAACAAUAGUGAAACUCCGUCUCAAAAAGAAAAAAAGUUUCCUUAGAAUGGAAAAUAUUCAUUCAUGAGCUCUUUUGGCAAUCCGUCAUCAGUAUAUUCUGAAAACCAAUAAGAUGUUGCCAAGUUGGGGGCGAGAGCUAUGUAAUGCAAGGCAUAUGCCUGAUGAAGUAUACAAAUACACCUGACCAGAAACUUUGUCUCCCACAUAAGUCUCUUCUAGGCACUGUCGGGGUACAUACUGAGCUGCUGCUUUGGCUGUAUUUUCUGUGCCUCAGAAUAACCAUUGUCCUGGUGUUCAUAUCCUUAGAGUUCAGUACAAAAUGUUGGAUAUCCAUUUAAUAGGUUCCAGGUUAUCUUAGUUGGAGUUUGGGGUAUUUGAAAACGUCAUGCCUUCAGGCUAUCAUUUCCCUCAGAAAGCUAAGUAAAUUUACUGCAUUCAUUUCUCAAAGAGUAAAAGUGCAGGUUGUAUGUGUCUAUGAACAUUUAAACAUGUUAAAAUGUUAAAUUUAACAUUUUAAAUUUAAACAUUUAAAUAUGUCUGUAACUUGAACAGUGUAGUUUCAGAAAGGACCACUGGGCUAGUGUAAUGCAGAAAAUGCUGGGUCUAGGAUUAGGAGAAAAUUGUGUUUAGUGUGUAUCAAUAAACAGCCCGUGGACCCAA